GUUCUGUGUUCGCUUGGGUAGAGGAAGCCGUGAGGCCGGAGCUUAGGUCGGGAAGGGAUGGAUCGCUGAGCCGAUAGCGUCCGCUAGGCUGUCUGCCUCGGUACCUGUUACUGCUGCUACUUCCUCGUUUGACACCUUCCUGGAAUCUCUCUUGAUUUUUGAGGAAAUACCUAGUAACAAACAUGACUGAGUUCUGGCUUAUAUCUGCUCCUGGGGAGAAAACCUGUCAGCAAACAUGGGAGAAAUUGCAUGCGGCAACUUCAAAGAACAAUAAUCUUGCUGUCACUUCCAAGUUCAAUAUUCCUGACUUAAAGGUUGGCACGUUGGAUGUCUUGGUUGGCUUGUCAGAUGAACUGGCUAAACUGGAUGCAUUUGUAGAAGGAGUGGUUAAGAAAGUAGCUCAAUACAUGGCUGAUGUAUUGGAAGAUAGCAAAGACAAAGUUCAAGAGAAUCUGUUGGCUAAUGGAGUGGACUUGGUUACUUAUAUAACAAGGUUCCAGUGGGACAUGGCCAAAUAUCCAAUCAAGCAGUCCCUGAAAAAUAUUUCUGAAAUAAUUGCCAAGGGAGUAACUCAGAUUGAUAAUGACCUGAAAUCUCGAGCAUCUGCAUACAAUAACCUGAAAGGAAAUCUUCAGAAUUUGGAACGAAAGAAUGCAGGAAGUUUGCUAACUAGAAGUCUAGCAGAAAUUGUGAAGAAGGAUGACUUUGUUCUUGAUUCAGAGUAUCUCGUCACAUUACUGGUAGUAGUUCCCAAGUUAAACCACAACGACUGGAUUAAGCAGUAUGAAACACUAGCCGAAAUGGUAGUUCCAAGGUCUAGCAAUGUUCUUUCAGAGGACCAAGACAGUUACCUGUGUAAUGUCACCUUGUUUAGGAAGGCAGUUGAUGACUUCAGACACAAAGCCAGAGAAAACAAAUUCAUUGUUCGUGACUUCCAGUAUAAUGAAGAGGAGAUGAAAGCAGAUAAAGAAGAAAUGAACAGGCUUUCUACUGAUAAGAAAAAACAAUUUGGACCACUUGUACGGUGGCUGAAAGUGAAUUUUAGUGAAGCAUUUAUUGCAUGGAUUCACGUGAAAGCAUUACGGGUUUUCGUUGAGUCUGUUUUAAGGUAUGGCUUGCCAGUGAACUUCCAAGCAAUGCUACUUCAGCCCAAUAAGAAAACUUUGAAGAAACUGAGAGAAGUAUUACAUGAAUUGUAUAAACAUCUAGACAGCAGUGCAGCAGCUAUUAUUGAUGCUCCUAUGGAUAUUCCAGGUUUAAACCUGAGUCAACAAGAAUACUACCCCUAUGUGUACUACAAGAUUGAUUGCAACUUGCUGGAAUUCAAGUGAAAAUGGGCUCCUCCCCCGACAAUCCUGUCCUUGUGUUUGUGUGUGCUAACAGAAAUAAGUUGCAGUAUGGUCGUACUUUUAACUCUAGUAUCCUUUGCUUGCUUCUUACGCCCUUUCCUAGGUGAAUUCUCCCACAGUGGUCUGUAUCUCAACAUUUUCUUUUUAAAGGAAAAAAUAUAUAUAUAUAGUUUCUUUUUAUUGAUCAGGUCUGUAAAUGUGUACUAAAAAAAUCAGAGUUUAUUUAUAAACAAAAUAGUUUAUUUAAAGAGAAGGUCUCUUCCUUAUUGAUAUCAUGGUAUGCAUUAAUUCCAUUUGUUACUAUUGUGCACAAAAGCCCUGUUCACAGGGGAAUGGUGUAAACAUUUAUACUGUUUUGUUCACUGUAUUUAGUAGACAUAACUGUUGAAUAGUUACUGAAUCAUGAUGUAAAGAAUAUGUGACCAUCUUCAGGUAUGGGAUUUCUGAACGUUUCAAAUUUCAAUCAAUGAGCACUGUCAACACCCACAGGAGAGAAUAAAAUUACCUGUGCAAAGGUGUAUUGUGGUGUGUGUAACUUAAGAUUACAGUUCUGUUUGAGAGUUAAAUGAUGUCAUAGCUCACUUGCUAUGCUGCUUCCAGGAUUUUGUUAUAUGCUGAGGUGUAACCAUUUGUGUUGUCUGACUUUCGUAUGAUUUAAUUGAGCCAAAUUUGGGUCAGAACACAAAUUUGAAGAUGACUUUUCAGUAUAUGAUGGGUAUUUACAUUUGAACACUAGAAUUUUAGGUCUCUCAAAUAAUUAAGAAUAGAGCCAGUUUUGAAUAAAGUCUAGCAGAACUAUGCAGCUUUAGUCAUUUGUUUUGUCUAAGUCUGUAUUUUAUGUGUUGUCUUCUUAAGAUCUAUAAUUUUGGCAUUUAUGUCAUUUGUGACAUAGUCUGAAAAUAGAGACAUUGUUGGCCUUUAAAAUCUCAGAAAUGAAUGACUUAAUUUAGUGUCCUGAAAGAGCUUUUAAAAGAGGAUUUUGUGGCAAUGUUUCUCUUACUACGUACUCACAGGUUUGCAAAUGGGAAAAAAGUUUACAUUUCAGUUUAGGGGCAUAUCUAAGCUAUGCUAUUCCCUUUAGAAAAUUAGCCUCCAAAAUCUUUUGUUUCAAAAUAUUAUAUUAUUUCAUAAAUAAUUUCAAGCAAAUACAGACAUCCACAAUGUAGAACAUGAGAGACCCCCUCCCUCAAUUUCCACCUCCCAAGGGAAGUUUAUGUAUUUUUCUAGGCCCUUUUCUAUGUCUUUACAUCUCUGUCUCACACACACACACGUAUACACACACACAGUUUAUUUUUAAUAAAAUAGGAUUAUACCACACACAUCCUGUCACUUGCUUUUUUGCUUAAGAGUAUAUCUAAGAGAAUCCUUUGUGUCAGUGAAGCUGGAGCUACCUCAUUCUUUUAACUGGCUGCGUGGCGUUCCAUUGAGUGUCUGUCAUCAUGUGUUUAGCCGAGUGGAUGGAUAGUCUGCUUGUUUUUAGUUUUUGCUCUUAACAAACACUGCUGCAGUCAGCAUCCUUGCACAGAUUUCUUUGUAUACUUGUAUUAGUAUUUCUGUAAGAUCUGAGAAGUGGAAUUUGUAGGGUCAUAGGUUAUGUACACUUAAGUUUUUGACACUCACUGCCAAGUCAUCUGUCAGAAUUCUAAACUAAAGACAUGUUUGGAGUGUGGAUUUAUCUUCAGUUUUUCUUUGGACAAGAGGAAGCUGUGAAAGAUUUUGCUAUCAGAAAAUUUUGGUUCUUUGUCUUUUGCACAUGUUCUUUGAGUCUUAGUAUCUGUAACGUGGCGCUACUCUCUCUAUCAUGGGGGGGCAUGUUUUGACAUUAAAUUGACUUUUAAGAAAAACAUGUCACUAACCUGAAGCUCAGCCACACAGUGACUUUUAAGGUUUUAUUUAGACUUUACUGUUGUUCUCAUGAGAGUAGGUACAGACUGCAUAAGGUUUAGAAUCCCAGCAUAUGUCUGAAACGACGGGACUUUCACUGUGAUUUCCACCAGAGAAAUUAUAGCAGAGUGGCUGAGCAUGUGCUCUGAGGCCAGGCCCCAGCUCUGCUGCUGACGAGCUGUGUGGUCCUGGGCAGAGUGGUCUCCGAGUUCCAGUCCCUCCUCUGUAAAAUGGGCAUGAUUAGAGUGCCCACCGCAUUAGGGAUGUUGGGGUGAGUCAGUGUGACCCCACGUGCACAGAAAGUGCUGCGAGUGGUGCAUGGUGAGAGGUUGAUGCAGGUACUUAGCCCUUGGGGAACACAGGUAGUUCCUUUUCACUGUGUUUAAUUUGGGAAAAUCCAGAUCCACAUCAUUGUAGAGUCUGAGGGUUAGAAGGAAGUCAUUGUGUCUAACAUAACAACAGAGCAGUUUGUGUCACUGAGCUCCAGUCUGUGCUGGAUUAUUGAUAUUGUUGGUGGCGGUCACCAUUCCUGGAAAGGGACUGUCCCAAGCCACUUACCUUCCCGAGGAGUCUGCUGGUUCUCCUUGAGGAUAGUGCUUAGAUAACAGACUCAUUAAACAUUUACUGAGUGUCUGUCAGGGAUCAUUCACAUCCACAUCAUCCUCCCGGCCCCUCCCCGUGUUGUUCAUGGAGGGAGUACUGGCGGUCCCCAUUUUCAUGUAUGGAGACUUCAGGUGAAAGAAGUUAAGUGAAUUCUUUGUUGAGUCACAAAUCUUGAGCCAGUCAGAAUUUGAACCUAAGAUUUUUGACUGCUGGUUGUCACACUUCCCGCCCCACACUCAACUGUUGUGUGAAUGAGCCAGACACAUUGCUUAACCUGAGUCCGAGAUGGACAAUGGUAUAGGAAAGAUAUUCGGUAUGGAGAAUCAGAUGUUAACUUGUGUUGCUAUUUUUGUUUUGUUUUGUUUUGUUUUGUUUUUGAGACAAGGUCUUGCUCUGUCACCCAGGCUAGAGUGCAGUGGCAUGAUCAGGGCUUACUGCAGCCUCACCCUCGAUUUCCUGGGCUCAAGCAAUCCUCCCACCUCAGCCCCCAAGUAGCUGGGCCUACAGGUGCGUGCUACCACGCCUGGCCAAUUUUUUAAAUUUUAGCACAGAUGAGGUCUCACUAUGUUGCCCGGGCUGGUCUCGAACUCCUGAGCUCAAGGGAUCCUCCCGCCUCAGCCUCCCAAAGUGCUGGUGUUACAGGCAUAAGCCACCACGCCUGGCCUGUGUUGCUAUUAUAUUUGGCAGGAACCCAGAGUCCAGAACAUUUCAUCUAUGAUGGGUUAGAUAAUGUGUCUAGUUGUUUGCAUGCCAAUUUCAGUAGCCUCAGUUAUUCAACCUAGGAGAUUUUUCUACCUCUUUACUACCCUGCUGAAGUUGCUCUUCAGCAGAAAAUCUUUGUGGAACACAUUCCACACUUUGAAAUCUUCGUGGAACAAAAGAUAUUUGUGGAACCAAUCUUUGUGGAACAUAUUCCAGCUUUUUGAAUGAGUGCAUAUCCAGUAGUACCUUUAAAGUAACACUUUGUACAUAACAAAUACUCAGCAAAUGUGAAACUUUAUUUGCUCUUACUUCAAAAUUAGUCCAAAAUGUUGGAAAUAAAAUAUAAGACAUUGAUCUAGAUAUGAGGUUUUUCUCCUUCAUUCUCAGCUGUCGAAGAAAUCAAAGUAGCAUAUGCACAAGGUUAAAAACCACAUAUACAAAUACUAUAGAACAGCUUAUAAUGAAAACCUUGCCUGCCUUUAUAAAAAAUGUGAUUAUCUUCUUCUGUUAAUGUCAAUAAAAGAUGGUUUGUCCUAGAAGGUCUAUAAAUGGUAUUAUGUUCUGGAGGAAACCUAGCAAAAACUUUGCUAGUUUAGUACUUGUCUCUAAAUUGAUGUUCACCCAUUUCAAUAUUGCACUUAUUAAUGGUCUUUAUUUUUCUAGCAUAGAUAACAAUUGAUUCUUUAGAUUCAUAUAUGGAGGUAAUUCUUGCUUUCUAAAGAAAGGAAUAUGGCACAUUGGAACCAUUUUAUUCACCAGUGGAUUUACCCUUAGAGUAUUUUUAGAUCUGAGCUGAUGACUUGUGAGAGAAAAAGGGAACAGAGUAAAGCCAUGGAAGCCAUGAACAGUAAGAGACUGCCGCCUGGCAUGGUUUCUUCUUCUGCAGAAGAUGAAACUGAGGAGAAACAAGACAACAUCCUUCAUACCAGGAAUGGUCAAGAUAAUGCAAGAAGAAAAAAGCUUUCAAACAAAUCAGAAGGCAGUCAACAAACAGAAAGGGGGACAUUCCUUCCCUGGCAGUUACUCAAAACUGAAAUUGCUUAUUGUGUACACCGGGGCUUGUACUUGGGGAAUUUAAUAAAAAUGCUCAUUACCAA